AGUGACAAUUAAAGAUGGCUGCGCCCAUGUAACAUCACUAGCGACCGGUGACCUCUUUUUCCCCCUUGCCUGGCUCCUGUGGUGGCAGGCUGGGCACGAGGACCAUGCUGGGCCGGAGCCUCCGAGAACCUGACUUUGAAACCAAAAGUUGGCUAAGGAGAAGAAUGUCAUGUCCUCCACCUGUCCUCAAGCUGAUCAGUGCAUCACCCUUCAUCCACUACACUAAGUGUAGAGGUUUCUGCGGCACUGAAACAAGGCCAAAUUACACCAACAGAGCUCUGUCAAAAAUGUCUCUCUCUUAUCAAGAAGACCAAGUUUCUAAAUGCCUACAUUACUGUGUCAGAAGAGGUGGCCUUAAAACAAGCUGAAGAAUCAGAAAAGAGAUAUAAGAAUGGACAGUCACUUGGGGAUUUAGAUGGAAUUCCUAUUGCAGUAAAAGACAAUUUCAGCACUUCUGGCAUUGAGACAACAUGUGCAUCAAAUAUGCUGAAAGGUUAUAUACCACCUUAUAAUGCUACAGUAGUUCAGAAGUUGUUGGAUCAGGGAGCUCUACUAAUGGGAAAAACAAAUUUAGAUGAGUUUGCUAUGGGAUCUGGGAGCACAGAUGGUGUAUUUGGACCAGUUAAAAACCCCUGGAGUUAUUCAAAACAAUAUAGAGAAAAGAGGAAGCAGAAUCCCCACAGCGAGAAUGAAGAUUCAGACUGGCUGAUAACUGGAGGAAGCUCAGGUGGGAGUGCAGCUGCUGUAUCGGCGUUCACAUGCUACGCGGCUUUAGGAUCAGAUACAGGAGGAUCGACCAGAAAUCCUGCUGCCCACUGUGGGCUUGUUGGUUUCAAACCAAGCUAUGGCUUAGUUUCCCGUCAUGGUCUCAUUCCCCUGGUGAAUUCGAUGGAUGUGCCAGGAAUCUUAACCAGAUGUGUGGAUGAUGCAGCAAUUGUGUUGGGUGCACUGGCCGGACCUGACCCCAGGGACUCUACCACAGUACAUGAACCUAUUAAUAAACCAUUCAUGCUUCCCAGUUUGGCAGAUGUGAGCAAACUAUGUAUAGGAAUUCCAAAGGAAUAUCUUGUACCGGAAUUAUCAAGUGAAGUACAGUCUCUUUGGUCCAAAGCUGCUGACCUCUUUGAGUCUGAGGGGGCCAAAGUAAUUGAAGUAUCCCUUCCUCACACCAGUUAUUCAAUUGUCUGCUACCAUGUAUUGUGCACAUCAGAAGUGGCAUCGAAUAUGGCAAGAUUUGAUGGGCUACAAUAUGGUCACAGAUGUGACAUUGAUGUGUCCACUGAAGCCAUGUAUGCUGCAACCAGACGAGAAGGGUUUAAUGAUGUGGUGAGAGGAAGAAUUCUCUCAGGAAACUUUUUCUUAUUAAAAGAAAACUAUGAAAAUUAUUUUGUCAAAGCACAGAAAGUGAGACGCCUCAUUGCUAAUGACUUUGUAAAUGCUUUUAACUCUGGAGUAGAUGUCUUGCUAACUCCCACCACCUUGAGUGAGGCAGUACCAUACUUGGAGUUCAUCAAAGAGGACAACAGAACCCGAAGUGCCCAGGAUGAUAUUUUUACACAAGCUGUAAAUAUGGCAGGAUUGCCAGCAGUGAGUAUCCCUGUUGCACUCUCAAACCAAGGGUUGCCAAUAGGACUGCAGUUUAUUGGACGUGCGUUUUGUGACCAGCAGCUUCUUACAGUAGCCAAAUGGUUUGAAAAACAAGUACAGUUUCCUGUUAUUCAACUUCAAGAACUCAUGGAUGAUUGUUCAGCAGUCCUUGAAAAUGAAAAGUUAGCCUCUGUCUCUCUAAAACAGUAAACAUAUCUUACAAAUUAAAAUGACUUUUAGGCUGGGUGCAGUGGCUCACACCUGUAAUCCCAGCACUUUGGGAGGCCAAGGCGAGCGGAUCAUGAGGUCAGAAGAUCUAGAACAGCCUGGUCAACAUGGUGAAACCCCGUCUCUACUAAAAAUACAAAAAUUAGCCAGGCUUAGUGGCGGGCAUCUGUAGUCCCAGCUACUCAGGAGGCUGAGGCAGGAGAAUCACUUGAACCCUGGAGGUGGAGGUUGCAGUGAGCCGAGAUCAUGCCACUGCACUGCACUCCAGCCUGGGUGACAAAGCAAGACUGUGUCUCAAAAUAAAUAAAUAAAAUAAAAUAAAAUGACGUACAGAGAUUCUAUAUUCUAGAGAGUCAAAUGGUCUUGCUCAAUUCUUGUAAUUAGGUUCUUGUUAAUACAGUCAUUCCAUGGAAUUACUUUUUAAAAUUCCUGUGACAAUUAAUAAUAAAUAACGUGUCAGCAUUUAGUAAGCAUCCACUAAGUGUACAAUACUUCUACAAUAACACAAGAUACCUGUUCCUCAAAGACAAUGCAUUCUGCCAUAAUGUUCAUUAAAGAGUUUACAGUAAAAAUAAGAUUAGGGAUAAACUUCUCAAAAAUUGUACAUCUGUGUAACUAAAGCACUAACAAAAACAUGAAUAGUCCUUCUAGAGGUAACUUGGAUAGCCUAGGCAGGCAACUUAUCAUGUGGUGAAGGCCGCCUCAGGGGUUGUUAAAAAUGCACAGAAACAAUUGAGUGCGAUUAUUGGCUUCUGAGCGCUGAGCAGAGCAGGUGGAAGAGGAACUUUGAGCACAGGAGGAAAUGCAACCAGUCAGGGCCCAGAAUCAUGCAAAUCUCAGGGGUAUGCCUCUCUGGGGAGGAGCUCCACUUGCAGGGACUCCUUUUAUUUCCCUAAGAAAGAGCUGAAAUGACUGAGAACUUUCCUUUCCUCCUUAGAGUUACAAUUUUACUUCUGCUAUUCCGGAGCCCAUGCCUAGAAGCCAGAACAACUCCAUGUUACACUGAGUUCAUGCUCCUAUUUACUGAUCACAAAUGAGCUCAUUAAUGUCAUCGAAACAUUUAUUGUAACCUAACAGACCAUCACAGAUUGGAAACUUGGUAGAUAGCAGAGCAUGGUAUUAGUGAAAAAGGUUCAAAAUACACAAGUAACAUACACUCUGAAAAACAUGCAGAUAAUUUGCUGAUGAAGCAGAAGAGGGGAUGCGCAUGGCAAGAACUUGCCUUACCCCAGAUUCUCUAUAUCUCAUGGUUUCCUUUUCCUCUUGACUGUCUUUACGAGUGUUUUUUAUUUGGGACCCUCGAGCCCAGAGAUAUUAAUGGAUAUCUGUAUUCAAUAUUUGACAAAAUCUAAUGGAAACCAUCCAUUUACUCAUGAUAAGGCUUCAUCACUGGAUUUCUGUGUCUUCACUAGAACACCAUUGUCAUCUCAUAUUGAUCAGGUAUUUUAAUCUAGCACUUACAUAUUGUUGAUAAAUGAAAGCUGAAUUGUUACUUAAUAAAUUCACUUUGUUUAGUAAAAAAAAAUUGUUUUCUAAAUAUGACGUUCAUGAAGAGAAAAUAAUGAGUCAGAAUCAUCUGCAGAACCACUGGAAUGUUUCAUCGUCACCUGUUAGUUUUCAUAAACAGUUUUCUGUCCUCUCUGAGAUCCUCCCGCUCCCAAAUACUCAACCUGAUUAACUUCACAUAAAAGUCUUAUGUGCCAGGCUUAGUAAUAUUCCUAUAGAUUUUGACUCUGAAUCCCUGAAAGAGGAAGAAAUCCAUGAGAGAAAAUUGCAUUACUUUAUAGCAAGAGGAAACCGUUUUAAGUUUUUUAAUUGCUCAGACACCACAACAUCCUAGAUGGAGGAAACCAUUUUAGUUGAAGGAGCAAAUAUGAUGUCAAAAGCAAGUAAAUAAACAAACCGUUGCCCCAAUCUGUUUUUAUGUAAUGAAUUUAAAAAAAAAGAGAGAGAGAGAGAGAUGGGCUCUCCCUGUGUUGCCCAGGCUAGUCUCAAACUCCUGGGCUCAAGUGAUCUGCCUCCCUCAGCCUCCCAAAGUGCUGAGAUUAAAGACGUGAGCCACCACACCUGGCCGAAAUAAUAAUAUUCAAUAUUAUAUAUUCAAUGAUAUUAUUCAGUAUUCAAUAUUAUUUCAAAUAAUAUUAAAUCUCUUGUUCCUGUAUCUCUACAUGAGCUGCACUAAUAAUUUGAAUCUGGAAAUUAAAAAGUGAAACAUUUACCGUUCUCAUAUACUGAUACCCAACUACCAUGAAAUGAUACCUAAUUUGUUUUUCUUUUCUCUUCAUUUUUACUCUUAAUCUAGUAGGUCUCAUUUUGCCAAGUCACUGUCUGGGAAUUUAAGUGGCAAAUACUUUCUUUGUCUCAGCUAAUUAAACUCUAAAAUUAUUAGCAACAGAA